UAGAGUGCAGUGGCAUGACCAUGGCUCACAGCAGCCUCAGCCUCCCUGGCUCAAGCAAUCCUCCCACCUCAGCCUUCUGGUAGCUGGGACCAUGGGCACAUGCCACCACAUUCAGCUAAUUUUCUUUUUAUAGAGACAGGGUCUCGUCAUGUUGCGCAGGCUGGUCUCCGGGGCUCAAGUGAUCUGCCCGCCUUGGCCUCCCAAAGUGCUGAGAUUACAGGGGUGAGCCACUGUCCCAAGCCCAGAUUAAUUUUUUAAUUUUGCCGUGUGUAAUCAUCUGUAAGUUUCCUUCAGGUUGAUUGUAGCAUAAUGCCUUUAGAAUUAUUACUUUAAUAUGAACUCGUUAUUAGCCAUAAAUCUCUGAUCUACUUCUGUUUGACACCUAAGAUGUCCCUGAAUUGCCUCCUUAUGACCCCAACUUACAUUUGGAAACUAAAAACUAAUUUAAGUGUAAACAUAGGGAAAAUAUAAUUGAAAACAGGAGUAUUUUACAAAUGCAGUGCUUUUUAAUAUGAAAAUAAGUGCUGUUUAUGCCUCUCUCUUUUCUAAUUACUAUGGAAGAAGGUUGACUAAGGAAAUGUUAAGAAAAAAAUGCCACUCCAUUAUCACAACUAAAUAAGAUGCAUUUUCUACCUUCAAAAUACAGUUUUAAAAUGUAUUAAAAUUCAAAUGACCAGCCUUCAGGUUUACUUCAUGGGCCCUCCAAUAUUAAUUAUUAAUAAUAGUAAUUGAAAAAUCAGCUUUUCAUCCUAGUAAGUGGUCUAAACUACUUGAAAGAAUCAAUCUUACUUGUGGGUAAUGCCUCUGCUGUUACUGAUUGUCCUUUGAAUUACAAUAUUCAUUUAUGCUUCACUUAAAUAAAAUCAAGGACUUCAGAGGACCCUUUUAGUGCCCUUGAAAUGGGUAGUGUAAGUGGUGUUUAGUGUCUUAGAACAGCUAUUAUCUUUAAAAACUGAAUCAACAAUUUCCACAAGCUGUUUUGAUCUCCUAUUCUUACACUGAAAAUGAAGGAGGAACUUAGGUUGUCAAAAUACAACAUAAUUGUAUGUGCCCCAUUCUUCUGCACUUCUAAAAGGAUGAGUGAGUUGCUUACGGAUCAGCCCACAUGUGCUCUGUGAUGAAAACUGAAAGCAAGUGACAGCUAGGUGGUCAAUGUCCUGUUAUCAAGGAGGAAACAGUGGCAAUGAAAACCAAAGCAUUAAAUAAUCUGAAAGGUCAUUUGUAUUUGGCUCUAGGAAGUGUUUUUUAUUUUUUCAACAUGAGUAUGUCUUAUAGUCUCUGAAUUUACUUAAGAAAAGUAAAAGCUUUGUACACAUACAUAUACAGAAAGAAGGCAUUCCAUGAAAACCCAUUUAUAGGCACUGCCUCCUCUCUCCUGUGCUACUUUUCUUCAGUUCCUCUCAGCUCACUAUUCUAAUUUAGAAAAGACAAAUGACUUGUUUUUUAUUUAGUUGGGUUUUUUUUAAGUUCAUAUACAGUGUUAAAUGGUUAGGGAUUUUACAUAGGUCUUCAGUUUCAUGUCUUGAUUGUCGGCCCUUUGUGACUGCGAUCAGUAAGAACUUUUAGGAAUGCUCUGUAGGGCAAGGUAGUAGAGUGGAGACAACAUGAACUGUAUGCCCAGAAGACCAGAGUUCAAUCCUGACUCUUAUUUGUUGAUAAUUUUAACCUCUCUCAACUACAGUGUAGUGAUUUAAGGACAUGGUUUUUCUGAAGACGCAGACAAUUCACAGUCAGGACUUCCAAGCUCCAGACCAGUGUAACCAACAUAUACUCUGCAUCUCCACUUGGUUAUCUCAAAAGUAUCUCAAACCCAACAUGUGUGAACCUAACCUCUUGCUCUUCCCGCCAAAUUAUUAUUUGCCCUGUGUUCCCUCCUGUUGGAGGGCACCAAGAUCUAUGCGGUUAUACAAAUAAGAAGUCUAGGAAGUCAUCUUGGACACUUUGAUCUGCUCCAUUCUCCUUCAUCUGACUCAACCAGAUUUUUUAAAAAAUGGAUUUGGCCAACCAUGGACUUAUUCUACUGCAACAGUUAAACGCUCAGCGAGAGUUUGGUUUCCUGUGUGACUGCACGGUUGCAAUCGGCGAUGUAUACUUCAAGGCACACAAAUCAGUUCUUGCUUCAUUCUCCAAUUACUUUAAGAUGUUGUUUGUCCAUCAGACCAGUGAGUGUGUCCGCUUGAAACCAACUGACAUACAGCCCGACAUCUUCAGCUAUCUCUUACACUUGAUGUACACUGGGAAGAUGGCGCCUCAGCUCAUCGACCCGGUUCGAUUAGAACAGGGCAUCAAGUUUCUGCACGCCUACCCGCUCAUUCAGGAAGCCAGCCUCGCCAGCCAGGGAGCCUUUUCUCACCCUGACCAAGUUUUCCCACUGGCUUCUUCAUUGUAUGGCAUUCAGAUUGCAGAUCAUCAGUUGAGACAAGCCACCAAGAUUGCUUCAGCACCUGAAAAACUCGGGCGAGAUCCACGGCCACAGACCUCCAGGAUAAGCCAGGAGCAGGUCCCUGAGGCCUCACAGCUCUCCCAGCUGACUUCAAAUCUGGCCCAGGUGAAUCGGACAAAUAUGACUCCCUCAGACCCCCUGCAGACCUCGCUGUCUCCAGAACUUGUUUCCACUCCUGUUCCUCCCCCUCCUCCCGGGGAGGAGACCAAUCUGGAAGCAUCUUCCUCCGAUGAGCAGCCUGCGUCCCUCACAAUAGCCCACGUCAAGCCAAGCAUCAUGAAGAGGAAUGGGAGCUUUCCAAAGUACUAUGCCUGCCACCUGUGUGGACGGCGCUUCACUCUCCGGAGCAGCUUACGUGAACACCUCCAGAUCCACACAGGAGUACCUUUCACAUCUAGCCAACAGGGAGAAAGUCGCGUCCCCCUGACUCUCUGUAGCAAUGCAGCUGACCUCGGGAAAGAUGCCAUGGAAGUGCCUGAAGCCGGGAUGAUAAGUGACAGUGAGCUGCAGCACAUCUCUGAUUCUCCCAUCAUCGAUGGGCAGCAGCAGUCGGAAACCCCACCCCCCUCAGACAUUGCUGACAUUGACAACCUGGAGCAGGCCGACCAGGAGAGGGAGGUGAAGAGGCGGAAGUACGAGUGCACAAUAUGUGGACGCAAAUUUAUCCAGAAAAGCCACUGGAGGGAACACAUGUACAUACACACCGGGAAGCCUUUCAAGUGCAGCACUUGUGACAAAAGCUUUUGCAGGGCCAACCAGGCUGCCCGCCACGUGUGCCUCAACCAGAGCAUCGACACUUACACCAUGGUGGACAAACAGACUCUGGAACUCUGCACAUUUGAGGAAGGGAGUCAGAUGGACAACAUGCUGGUGCAAACAAACAAACCCUACAAAUGCAACUUGUGUGACAAAACAUUCUCCACUCCCAAUGAGGUUGUUAAACAUUCAUGCCAAAACCAGAACUCGGAUGUUUUUGCCCUAGACGAAGGGCGAUCCAUUCUCCUGGGCAGUGGGGACUCGGAAGUAACGGAGCCUGACCACCCAGUGUUAGCUUCCAUCAAAAAGGAACAAGAAACCGUCUUACUAGACUGAAUGUCACUUAUCUUUUUAAAAAACUCUCAUUUUUACAAAGACUAUCUUCCCUCCCUUCCCUGAAUUCAGAACUGUAGUUCUCCAUGGCAUGAUACAAACAGGUCCUUGUUCUCUUCUCCUCUUCCCCUUUUCCACAUCCCAGCCCCACCUCUGUAAAGGCUUUGUGCAUUAUAAACCUGGAAUGUAUCGACUUUCUUUCAGGGGAUAUUGGAAAGAUAAUGGUCAUUAUACUUAUAAACUCAAAUUUUGAGAGGUUUUAGAUUAUUCAGAAGCAUACUUGGAACUAAUGAAGGGUAUAUAAUAAAACAACUGGAAUCCAAUUUGGUAAGCUAAAAUUAUGACUUUCCCUGGGUAAAAAGUCUUCUCAGAAAAACAAUGUCAGAAAAUAACAGCGUGCUGCUUAGAAAUACGGCUGGGCUCUGUACUAUGCAAAAUCUAGAAAGUGUGGGGAAACUUUAAACCCAAGAAAACGUUCUUAGUAUUCAUCCUCCAGGUGUCUUACUUCAGAAUGCAUCCUUUGAGAUUAUGUCCACUUAAGAGAAAUCAUCAGUUAAGAAAUCUACUUUAACAAAACAAAAAGGAGAAAAAGUAAUAAUGUGAUGGCAAUCUUAAUUUUUGGGUACAACAUGACAAGCUGUGAGUUUGUGUGUUUGUAAGAGAAAAAUGUGUGGGUACUUGCUAAUAAACAGGUGAAUUAAUGCACAUCCUUAUCUCAUUGCUGGCUUCUUUCCAAGUUGAGCAACAACAAAAUGCUGUAUUUGAGUUUCUGACAAAUUUGUUUUAAAAAUCAAAUUUGAAUGUACUAUUCUAUAAAUUGCCUUUCUGAAUAGAACAUGACAUGCCAUUUUCUAGCAGCUGCCAGUGAUAAUUUGUUUUACACUAACUUUUAAAUCAGUGUGUGUACUGCAGGGAAAAGGAUAUAGGAAUACUCAUCUUACAGGGGAAUUUGUGACCAGAAGAUGUAGUAACUUCAAUGACUGAAAGUCAAUGCUGAUAGUUUACUGGCAACAUUAAUUGAAGCAUCAAAAAUAAAUGGCAAAGAGAAAUCAGGACAAAAAAUCUAAUUGCUGUUUGGGAAAAAACUUGAUUUUGAUGUUUAUUCUCCAGGUUUUUGGUUGUUUUUUUUUCUUUCUUCUUUCUUAAUGCCUGAAAUUUUCUCCAUUGGCCCGAAAGCAGUAAAAAUUGUUCAUUAAUCUUCCGUUAGGCCAAUAAAAGAAGGGCCUCACAAGACAAAACAGGAGCCAGAAGUAAGGACUGAAGGAGAAGGGGAGAAUAGCUAAUAGCUAUAGUAUAUGUAUAUGUUAAAAACUGAAUAUCCCAUCAUCCUAUUUCAUGUAUAGUUGAGUUCUCAAAUUUGUAAGUUUUUAUACAUCCUUUCAUUGAAUAAACGUUUAAUUAAAUGAGUA